GCCACCGCUUCCGCCGGGCCAUGGGGCCGCGCGUGCUGCAGCCGCCGCUGCUGCUGCUCCUGCUGGCGCUGCUGCUGGCGGCGCUGCCGUGCGGUGCCGAAGAGGCCUCGCCGCUGCGCCCCGCGCAGGUCACGUUGUCGCCGCCGCCGGCCGUGACGAACGGGAGCCAGCCGGGCGCGCCACACAACAGCACGCACACGCGUCCGCCGGGGGCGUCGGGCUCGGCGCUGACGCGCUCCUUCUACGUGAUCCUGGGCUUCUGCGGCCUGACCGCGCUCUACUUCCUGAUCCGGGCGUUUAGGUUGAAGAAGCCUCAGCGGAGGCGAUACGGCCUCCUCGCCAACACUGAGGACCCCACGGAGAUGGCCUCGCUGGACAGCGACGAGGAGACGGUGUUUGAGUCCCGGAAUCUGAGAUGAUGCUGAGCCAGGGAGGCGGCCCUUCCAGCAGCCAUGAGGGAAGGACAGGAGAUGGGGCCCACCCCAGUGCCCAGCAACCCCCUGCUCCACCGCUCAUUCCCCUGCUGGCCCCGGGGCUGGUCUCACCCAGUGCCAACCCGAGAGCUCCUUUUGGAACCUGCACAGCCCGCCGACCUGUUGCCACCUGCACCCACCGCUGGACCAUGCAGCCUCGCCUCCUGGAUGCUGUCCCAGCCUGGCCGAGGGUCCCAGGUGAAGACUGGAGGGACCCCAACAGCCACCGCCCAGGACGCUGAGGCUCCCUUGCCUGACUGUGACUUGUGCCUCUCUCCUGCCCCCGUGGGGACAUGGCAGCCCAGAGCCAAGGCUGGGUGGGCAGGUGACCCAAGGAACCUUUCUGGGAACACCUUCUCGCCGGGCUGGGAACAAUAAAUGCAGCCAUGUCUCUGCA